CUAUGACCAAAUGUAUGGGGCUUUUUCCCACACACCAAGCAAGCAAGCAGUUCUGCAGAGGGCACACAGUGUCCUCUAACUCAGUUUGAUUCUGAUACUAUCUACCUGGAAACAGCAUCAGAUCCCACAGUUUGAGGGCUCAAUCCCACAAGACUUUCCCCCAUUUCAGACACCAAUCACAAGUAAUAGUUUGUCACCUACACCUCUGACCAAGUGGCUAUAAAUUGGUGUUCCCACUACCCUCUCCUUGGACUCAACUGAUUUGCUAGAGCAACUGACAGAACUCAGGAAAACACCUACAUUUACUGGUUUAUUUUAAAGGAUAUUAUAAGGGAUACCAAUGAACACCAGAUGGAAGAGAUGCAUAGGGCAGGGUCUGUGGGAAGGGUGGCAGAGCUCCCAUGCCCUCCCAACGUGCACCACCCUCCAGGAACCUCUAAAUGUUCAGCUGCCCGGCAGCUCCCCACACCCAGUCCUUUUGAGUUUUUAAUGGAGGCUUUAUUAUGUAGGCAUGAUUGAUUACAUCAUUGGCCACUGGUGAUUAGUUUAACUUUUAGCCCCUCAUCUCCUGGAGGUUGGGGCGUGGGACUGAAAAAUCCUAUCCUCUAAUCAUACCUUGGUCUGUCCUGUGAGCAGCCCCCAUCCCGAAGCUUCCAGGGGUUCCCCAACCACUAAUCAUCUAAUAAGCAUACAAAAAACACUCUUACCACUCUGGAGAUCUCAAGGGUUUGGGGAGCUAUAUGUCAGGAAACAGGGAUGAAGACCAAACAUGUAUUUCACUGUAUCACACCUGUUCUCACCCCUCCCCAGAUCUUCUCUCAAUUAAUAUGAGACAAAAAAAUGAGUCUGACUUCUUGACCAAAAUAUCAGUUCUGUCCUUAGCAGCUUUAUGGAGGACAGAUUUAGUUUAAAUUCCUUAGGCAUUAUGCCCCUGUGGCUCCACUCAAUCAGAAAUAGGGUCAACGGCAAGGUCAGGGCCUCCAAUCUGGGCAAGAGGGAGGCAGCCACGGUAUCCACAAGUGUAAUUCUCUGAGUGCUGGUUGCUGGGAGGGGCACACCCUGGGCCAGCAAGUCACUUGGCCAAGGGUGGCCAACUGUGAGGUAGCACUGCCCUUUACUCCCUAAAAAAAUGUGAAUCUCUUUGGAGCAAACUCCUCUUCAGAAAUUUGAGCACUUGUUUUCUGAGCAAGGGAAUCAGCUAAUGCUUUUGACUCCCCAUCCAUCUUCCUGCAUCCUCGUCCCACCUCUCCUGCCCCCACUCACCUGGCUCUGUCUUUACCCACACCAUGGUUUUGGUACAAGAACACCCUUUUCCCCAUAAGCUACAUUGGUCCAGGCCAUAAAAAUUCAUUAGUUCCCUUUCUUCAGGGGCCUUCUGAAAUGCUCCCUGGAGAACUCUUUAUUCACUUCUUUGCACAAGAAUCACAUAUGUGUGAACACUGGUAUUGGCCUUCUAACUCAGUUUCUUCAAACCAGGGUCCUGGUCUGGUUGCCCCUGUCUCCUCCCACUGAGUUUUAUCUCCACAUAAGUAUUGCUCACCAAGAACAGAGCUGUUGACACCACUGGGCCUCAAGCAUGCUGAAUGCAUUGCUGCCAACUGCUCUGCCUUAAGAAGGUUGGAAACUGAUGAGGGUGCCACAAAUUGUUCACCUCAGCCCUUCUGGGCUGGUUGGAGGAGGCCCUCUCAUGAAUCAGUCAGCAAAUGUUUGACCCCUACCAGGUGGUCCUGGUAAUAUGUGGUAUGAAUCAUGGUCCUAGAUGUCUGCCAUAGCAAAUAAAAAAGGAAGACAGGGAAAGAAGCUGUCGCCUACAGAGUGGCUUGAUGACAGCUGCCUCACUAAUUUAAAAAGCCAUGUGUAGUGCUUCCUAUUUCUCACUAUGUUUGGGUGAGUGGGAGAGGGAGAAAGAUUAUAUGGGCUUCGUUGUGACACUGUUCUUAGCCAGUGGGUCAAUAGAUGAGUUUUGGUUUUGUUUUUUAGAAGACAGGAUGAGAAGAGAGUGCCCCCUUCCACCUCCAACAUGGCAUGCCAUGCUAGGUGCUGAAGGAGUUCUCUAAGCAGGGAUGGAGCACCGUGCGUGUGUGUGUGUAUAUGUGCACGUGUGUGUGUACGUGUGUGUGUGUGGCAGGUCUAGAGGGUCGAUGGCUCUUUCCUGCCUCUUGCCCUUGGUAUGGGUACCUUAGUGAUGCAUCAUGGCCCUCCCUUAGGACACACAGCUUCGCAGUGCCAGUGAACCCACUCCUUUUGGCUCCUCCUCUGGAAUGAUAAGCCCAGAUGCCCAUGCUGCCCGUGAAGGGCUUCUUCUUGAACUGAAUGUGGAGGGCAUCUCUGGUCCCGGCCAUCUGCCAGUGACUCUCAUGUGCAUUCAUGUCCCUCUCUUCUCUCUGUCCUGUCUUCUCUGCCGCUGCCUCUUCUCUGCAGGUACACUUGCUGAAGGACCAGUUGGCUGCUGAGGCUGCGGCGCGGCUGGAGGCCCAGGCUCGCGUGCAUCAGCUUUUGCUGCAGAACAAGGACAUGCUCCAGCACAUCUCCCUGCUGGUCAAGCAGGUGCAAGAGCUGGAACUGAAGCUGUCAGGACAGAACGCCAUGGGCUCCCAGGACAGCUUGCUGGAGAUCACCUUCCGCUCCGGAGCCCUGCCCGUGCUCUGUGACCCCACGACCCCUAAGCCAGAGGACCUGCAUUCGCCGCCGCUGGGCGCGGGCUUGGCUGACUUUGCCCACCCUGCGGGCAGCCCCUUAGGUAGGCGCGACUGCUUGGUGAAGCUGGAGUGCUUUCGCUUUCUUCCGCCCGAGGACACCCCGCCCCCAGCGCAGGGCGAGGCGCUCCUGGGCGGUCUGGAGCUCAUCAAGUUCCGAGAGUCAGGCAUCGCCUCGGAGUACGAGUCCAACACGGACGAGAGCGAGGAGCGCGACUCGUGGUCCCAGGAGGAGCUGCCGCGCCUGCUGAAUGUCCUGCAGAGGCAGGAACUGGGCGACGGCCUGGAUGAUGAGAUCGCCGUGUAGGUGCCGAGGGCGAGGAGAUGGAGGCGGCGGCGUGGCUGGAGGGGCCGUGUCUGGCUGCUGCCCGGGUAGGGGAUGCCCAGUGAAUGUGCACUGCCGAGGAGAAUGCCAGCCAGGGCCCGGGAGAGUGUGAGGUUUCAGGAAAGUAUUGAGAUUCUGCUUUGGAGGGUAAAGUGGGGAAGAAAUCGGAUUCCCAGAGGUGAAUCAGCUCCUCUCCUACUUGUGACUAGAGGGUGGUGGAGGUAAGGCCUUCCAGAGCCCAUGGCUUCAGGAGAGGGUCUCUCUCCAGGACUGCCAGGCUGCUGGAGGACCUGCCCCUACCUGCUGCAUCGUCAGGCUCCCACGCUUUGUCCGUGAUGCCCCCCUACCCCCUCACUCUCCCCGUCUCCAUGGUCCCGACCAGGAAGGGAAGCCAUCGGUACCUUCUCAGGUACUUUGUUUCUGGAUAUCACGAUGCUGCGAGUUGCCUAACCCUCCCCCUACCUUUAUGAGAGGAAUUCCUUCUCCAGGCCCUUGCUGAGAUUGUAGAGAUUGAGUGCUCUGGACCGCAAAAGCCAGGCUAGUCCUUGUAGGGUGAGCAUGGAAUUGGAAUGUGUCACAGUGGAUAAGCUUUUAGAGGAACUGAAUCCAAACAUUUUCUCCAGCCGGACAUUGAAUGUUGCUACAAAGGGAGCCUUGAAGCUUUAACAUGGUUCAGGCCCUUGGUGUGAGAGCCCAGGGGGAGGACAGCUUGUCUGCUGCUCCAAAUCACUUAGAUCUGAUUCCUGUUUUGAAAGUCCUGCCCUGCCUUCCUCCUGCCUGUAGCCCAGCCCAUCUAAAUGGAAGCUGGGAAUUGCCCCUCACCUCCCCUGUGUCCUGUCCAGCUGAAGCUUUUGCAGCACUUUACCUCUCUGAAAGCCCCAGAGGACCAGAGCCCCCAGCCUUACCUCUCAACCUGUCCCCUCCACUGGGCAGUGGUGGUCAGUUUUUACUGCAAAAAAAAAAAAAGAAAAAAGAGAAAGAAAAAAAAGAAUGAAUGCAAGCUGAUAGCUGAGACUGUGAGACUGUUUUUGUCCACUCUUCUGAAUCACUGCCACUUGGGUCAGGGACCACAGCCAUUGCCACCCUUGGCCCAUCUCUCUGCGUGCGUGCCUUGAGCACACAUAUAAAAAGUGCCAUGUGCAAUUGUCUUAUCUUUUAUGAUCUAGGCUUUGCCUAGGGAUCACUACUCCUUAACGGGCUGGCUGGGGCAAUGAGGAAAAGCUCCUUUGCUCCUGUAAGGCCAUAAGUGGCUGUUAACAGAUUUUCAAAUGCCUGAAGAGAUUGCUGAGACCUGCUAGAGUCAUAUGUUCGGGGAAUUAAGUCUUUAUCCUAGACAACAAGGUACAGAUGCAAACUGCAGUGUUAUUGGAGGGUCAAUCGGCAAGGAUAUGAUUAUCCCAAAAUGGAGUUCAUCGACCCUAGCUUUCCUUUAGAUUAUAUAUAAAUAAAAGUGCAGUCCUCUUCUAAUGGCCACAGUUGGUUUUCUUGUAGCCCAGAAAGUCCAAAUUAAAGGAAAUAAAUUCAGUUUUAUGUUAGCCUUCCUUGGUGCAUCAGGGUGUCAGUGGAAAUAGGAUCAGGUGGUGUGUGUGUGUGUGUUUUGUGUGUGUGUGUACACAUGUGUUUAUAUAUACAUGUGUGAGGGAAAGUGUGUACAUAUAUGUAGGAUUGUAACCAGACGGAAAAGAACGAGGAUCUCCAGGGUGUUUGAAUCAGCAACAGAUUUGUGUUUUCUAACAUGCAUUUAGUUGGAGAGGCAUGGUUCUGUUUGUUUUGUUUUGAUCUAAUUUGCCAUUGGAAAUAGGUACAGUUACACAGAGAAGGAAGAACCAGGAAAGUGAGAUCCAUGAAACUAAAUGAGCAGCUGUCAGAAUCCAGUGUGGCUGAGCCUACCUAGCUUAUGAAAUCUAACCCAGGGUUCCCUGAGUCCAAGACCACUUAGAUUAUUAAGAUUUUGAACGUCCAGAGGAGUGAAAAGUCUGUUUUCUGACGUAAGCCGGAGCUGAGGAUAAAGCCAGAGGCCAGUGGAUUAGGUGUAUGGAAUGUGGAUGGAGAGGGCUUGUGUGGGAUGUGGCCAGGGAGUGGGUGAGGAAGGCCGCUUCUAAAUGGCCUGUAAAAACUUGAGAUUGGAUAGACGAAAGGAAAUGGAGAAAUUAAAGAAUUGGAGAAACUAGUUAUCUGUGUUGCUGACUUUGGGACCCAUCCAAGACUCCUGCCCUUGGGGUGUUCCAUGGUGGUUUCUUCCUGCCUGGGCGCCACCCUUUCCCCAGUUCAGGCCCUCCCUGGAGGACUAGUUUGUGUAUUGGUAUCCUCCCCAGUGGACCCAAACCAGCGCAUACUUGGUGUGUGGAGAUGGGAGACAAAGGACAGAUCUAGGAGCCUUGAAGGAUCACCAGCCACCGACCCUCCAUCAGGGCCAACUGGGCAGGAAAGGGAACAUUGCAGACCUGAUUUCCCGACGAUGUCACCCUGUCCUCCCUCCUUGCUUCUUGCUCUGCUAACUCAACUCUGCCUUCCUCUUUUUCAUUCUUCUACUCUGCCCUAUAUGGAGGACAAAUGGACACCAGGGGUGCUAACCUUAUUGGUGCCUGCCCCAGCCUACCCCAGGUGCCAGCAGACUCUCGUGCACAGGAGGCUCCCACAGUUAUGGAGCCAGGAAAGAAUUUCUCUGCACUGGAUGGACUGUAUAUUGAGAUUAAAAAUUAUAUUCCUUAUAUUCCUGCUUAUAUCAAUGCUCUCUCUGUAAAACCUCUUCCUAGCCUCAUUUCUCUCAACUGAUCUUGUUUAGGCGUUGUAUUCCUUUUAUUUACUCUUUGCUUGACUGCUUCCUCCUAACCCUCUACCCACUAGCACUCUACUUCCUAAAGCUGUUGUGUCAUUAACUCUGUUGGAUCAACUCUCUGGGAAAAGAUUCUGUUAAUGUAAGUGCACUUACUCCCUGGAUGUUGUCACUAGUCUAGUGGCUUUUGCUAAAUAAACCUUUCUUAUUUCUA